ACUCAGGCAGCAGCCCCUUCUUUCUUGCCCCAGUCUCCAGUUCUCCAGUGUUCACAGGUGAGCCUACCAACAGCCACUGCUCAUGAUGGAGGCCAUCAAGAAAAAGAUGCAGAUGCUGAAGUUAGACAAGGAGAAUGCUCUGGAUCGGGCAGAGCAAGCUGAAGCUGAGCAGAAGCAGGCAGAAGAAAGAAGUAAACAGCUGGAGGAUGAGCUGGCAGCCAUGCAGAAGAAGCUGAAAGGGACAGAGGAUGAGCUGGACAAGUAUUCUGAAGCUUUGAAGGAUGCCCAGGAGAAGCUGGAACUGGCAGAGAAGAAGGCUGCUGAUGCUGAGGCUGAGGUGGCCUCCUUGAACCGUAGGAUCCAGCUGGUUGAAGAAGAGCUGGACCGUGCUCAGGAGCGCCUGGCCACUGCCCUGCAAAAGCUGGAAGAAGCUGAAAAAGCUGCUGAUGAGAGUGAGAGAGGUAUGAAGGUUAUUGAAAACCGGGCCUUAAAAGAUGAAGAAAAGAUGGAACUCCAGGAAAUCCAACUCAAAGAAGCUAAGCACAUUGCAGAAGAGGCAGAUAGGAAGUAUGAAGAGGUGGCUCGUAAGUUGGUGAUCAUUGAAGGAGACUUGGAACGCACAGAGGAACGAGCUGAGCUGGCAGAGUCUAAGUGUUCUGAGCUGGAGGAGGAGCUGAAGAAUGUCACCAACAACCUCAAGUCUCUUGAGGCUCAGGCGGAGAAGUACUCUCAAAAAGAAGAUAAAUAUGAGGAAGAAAUCAAGAUUCUUACUGAUAAACUCAAGGAGGCAGAGACCCGUGCUGAGUUUGCUGAGAGAUCGGUAGCCAAGCUGGAAAAGACAAUUGAUGACCUGGAAGAUGAGCUCUAUGCCCAGAAACUGAAGUACAAGGCCAUUAGCGAGGAGCUGGACCACGCCCUCAAUGACAUGACCUCUAUAUAAUUAUCACCGUUUCUGCUCUGUUCUGGAUCUGCCCCCUUUACUCCUCGGGGAACCCAAGGCCCCACUCUCGCUCUGGAUUCCAUUUGGGUCAGCCUGGCUGGUCCCCAAGGCAUUAGGAUGGGGGAGCAAAAAGCAACUUAUGUAUUUUCUUCCACCCCCACCCCAAAUUAAAAUGUUAAGCUGCUGGAAACCUCAUGCCACCCUGCAUUUGUGUCAUUGACAAAGCUGUUGCUGUCCCUAAGAAGGAGCCUUGGGGGUGUGAUGUGGGGAAGAGCUAUUGUAGGCUCCCCCUCCUCUGACUUAUGUAAUCAAAGCCACUUUUGUGUGUGUCUAUUUUUUCUUGACAUUUAAACUCAGCUGAUCUGAUUCUACCAGAGUGAUGGAUUUAGUACAGGUUACUCAGGAUAGUAAUUUUAGUUAUACUCCUCAAGCUGAACAAGAUUAAAUUCCUUAUUUCCAGGUUCUUAAAUCAUCCUGCCUGCAGUGUUUCCAUUCUCUCUUCAGGUAUUCCUCCUUUGGUGUGGUGUCAUUGAGAAGCCAUUGAAGUGACUCUCAAUACACAUUCUGUACCCUUUUACCGGUGGUUCAAAUGGUGCAUCCUCAGAACACCCAGUGAACCCAAUACAUUAUUGCUAAGAUUGACUAAUUAUGUCAACUCCAGUCACAGAAAAAUACACAAUGGAUAGAAUUCUGGACGGUUUUUUUACUUUUUCUUCUUUAAACCUUUCUUACAUAUUUGAGACUUGCUACCAUUUGCCUGCUAGUGUGUGACUAGUGGGAUAUAAGAUAAGUGAUAAAUUAUUAUUGGGAAAACUAAAAUGACCAAUCAUGCAUAUUUCAAAUAAUGUGCAUAUGAGGCUAAUGAUUUAUUACAUACAUAAAUUUCUGCUAGUAAAAUUUUCCUUGGUUCAUAUUGUGGAAUUAAAUAUCAACAUUUUAGAAAUUCCCAUUAUAGGCCGGGCGUGGUAGCUCACGCCUAUAAUCCCAGCACUUUGGGAGGCUGGGGCAGGUGGAUCACCUGAGGUCAUGAGUUCGAGACCAGCUCGGCCAACAUGGUGAAACCCCGUCUCUACUAAAAAUACAAAAAUUAGCUGGGCAUGGUGGGUGGGUGCCUGUAAUCCCAGCUACUCGGGAGGCUGAGGCAGGAGAAUCGCUUGCACCUGGGAGGCGGAGGUUGCAGUGAGCGGAGAUCGCGCCACUGCAUUCCAGCCUGGGCAACAGAGAGACUCCAUCUCAAAAAAAAAAAAGGAAUUCGCAUUCCAAUUUACACAGCAGAGAUUUCUUAAUAGUAUAGCUGUGAAUUAUACUAAUCCAAGCACGUAAGUGUUGUUCACUUAGUACUUUAGUUUCCCAGCAGGGUAUGUAUUUAAAAUUUGCUUUUCUUUUAGCUGGGUGCAAUGGCACUUGCCUGUACUGCCUGUAGCUUCUUGGGAGGCUGAGGCAGGAGGAUUGCUUGAGCCCAGGAGUUCUGCACUGUAGUGUGCUAUGCAGGUCAGAUGUCCUCACUAAAUUUGGCAUCAGUAUGGUGACCUCCUGGGAGUGGAGAACAACAAGGUUGCCUAAGAAGGGGUGAACUGGCCCAGGUCGGAAAUGGAGCAGGUCAAAAUUCCUGUGCUGAUCAGUAGUGGGAUUGCACCUAUAAAUAGCCACUGUAGUACUCCAGCCUGGGCAACACAGCAAGAUUCCAUCUGUUAAAAACACUUUUGCUCUUCUUUUAAACAGAUAUAAUCAGGUAGGGAAGUUUUCCUUAAUCUAAAACUUUAAGUCAUAUCAAAUUCACGUUUCCUUUUGUCCAUUCCAUUUCUUACUGCCGCAUAGCCUUUGAGAUUAAGGUUCAGAUUCAUUUAUUCAGCUGACACUUCCUGGUAUCUUCUAGGUAUAGGAUAUUAAGAUGGAGACAGAAAUAAAGAUGGAGGCACCAUUCCUACUCUCAAGUUGCUUAGAAUCUACUAGGAGAGAAAACAUACAUAAAGCUACAGAUACUGUGUGAUGAAUGCCACAAAUAAUAGUGUUAUGGGAAUUGAGUAGAGGGGACGAGAUUGAUCCUAGUGGGAAUGAAUUGGAAAAACUCAUGGAAGAAGGCAUGUAAUGGGUACUUCAUAAACAUGUUAAAACUUUUUUCUUUUUUUCUUUUUUUUUUUUUUUUUGAGACGGAGUUUGACUCUUGUCACCUAGGCUGGAGUUCAGUGGCCUGAUCUCAGCUCACUGCAACCUCUGCCUCCUGGGUUCAAGCAGUUCUCCCACCUCAGCCUCCCGAGUAGCUGAGAUCACAGGCGCCUGCCACCACACCCAGCUAAUUUUUGUAUUAUUAGUAGAGGUGAGGUUUCACCAUGUUGGCCAGGCUGGUCUGGAACUCCUGACCUCAAGUGAUCCACCCACCUCAGCCUCCCAAAGUGAUGGGAUUACAGGCUUGAGCCACUGCGCCCAGCCAACAUGUUAAACUUGCAUAUUCAUUUUUAUUGGGUUCCAAAAGUGGAUUUUUGACAAGCAGAGUUGGGUUGUGGGAUAGUGAAUAUUGAGCAUUCCAUUAUUUAUUUAUUUUUCUCUUUUUGAGAUGGAGUCUCGCUCUGUCACCCAGGCUGGAUGGAGUGCAGUGGUGAGAUCAUGGCUCACUGCAACCUCUGCUUCUUGAGUUCAAGCGAUUCUCCUGUCUCAGCUUCCCGAGGAGCUGUGAUUACAGAUACCCACCACCAUGCCCAGCUGAUUUUUGUAUUUUUAGUACGGACGGGGUUUCAGCAUGUUGGCCAGGCUGGUCGCGAACUCCUGACCUCAAGUGAUCCACCCGCCUCUGCCUCCCAAAGUGUUGGGAUUACAGGCGUGAGCCACUGCACCUGGCCUGAGCAUUCCAUUUAAAGAGAAACAAAAUAAUAAAGGCAUUGAUAGAGAUGAGAAGGCCACAAUAGCUCUAAAGGUAGAUUUAGACAGAGUAGGGAACAGGUUGUGUCUUAAAAUGAGGCUGAGGAGUUAUAAUUUUACUUGGAGUUAAUGGGGAUGCCACUGGAGAUUUUGAAUAGGAUAUGUUGUGAUCUGAAUAACAUAUAAGAAGAAUUAAUUUGGUAACUAAUUUGCAGAUUAGCAAAGUGAUUCACUAACAUGGUGUUUCUCACAUUUCAGCCAUUUAUGUUACCAUUUUUGAUGGCUUUUUCCAUAUUCAUUGCUGCCUACAUUGUUUUCUUCAGAUCUACUCAUUUCCAGAUUUAUUUUGUUCUUACUUGACACAAUUCUAUUUUGAAAUCAAAGUUUUGAUGUGUUAGUGUUUUUUCCUAAUCACAUUAAAGUAACUAUAGCAGUGAAUACACCACACUUUGGAAAAAAUUGGGUUAGGUUAAUUUAGUUUUCUAGGAGAGAAUAAUCAGGGUCUGAGCUAGAGUAGUGGCAGGAGAGAUAGCACUAAAUAAAGACAGGCAUUGUGAAAGGCCUGGCCACUUGAUGUGAGGAGGAAAGACAAGGAUGACUGGUUUUUAGAGUAGGAGAAUUAGCCGGGUGCAGUGGCUCAUGCCUGUAAUCCCUGCACUUUAGGAGGCUGAGGUGAGAGGAUUUCUUGAAUCCAGGAGUUCGAGACCAGCCUGGCAAUAAAGUGAGAACCUGUCUCUACAAAAUAUAAAAACUUAGCCAAACAUGGUGGUGCGUGCCUGCAGUCCUAUCUACUUGGAGGGCCGAAGCCAGAGGAUCCUUUGAGCCCAGGAGUCUGAGGCUGCAGCAAGCUGUGAUCACACUGCUGCACUCCAUCCUGGGUGGCAGAAUGAGACCCCCCCCAAAAAAAGAGUAGGAAAGUGGUGGGGUUAAAGAUGUAGGGAGAUCAUGUUGUCCUGGUUUGGGGAGCUGGGGGAAGGGAAAGAAGAUACGGCUGACAAUCUGGCAGGUAUCUGGGUGAAAACAAAAUUCUAGGGCGUGAGGCAGAGAGGUUGACAUAAGAGAGUUGGGAAUCCAUAUGGGGUACAGGUAGUUUAUGCCAUGGAGGUAAAUUAGAACCAUGAAGGACAAUUGCAAAUACAAAAAAAAGAGGCCAGGCACGGUGGCUCACGCCUGUAAUCCCAGCACUUUGGGAGGCCGAGGUGGGCGGAUCACGAGGUCAGGAGAUCAAGACCAUCCUGGCUGACACGUUGAAACCCCGUCUCUACUAAAAAUACAAAAAAUUAGCUGGGCGUGGUUGCGGGCACCUGUAGUCCCAACUACUUGGGAGGCUGAGGCAGGAGAAUGGCGUGAACCCGGGAGGCGGAGCUUGUAGUGAGCUGAGAUUGUGCCACGGCAUUCCAGCCUGGGUGACAGAGCAAGACUCUGUCUCAAAAAAAAAUUAAACAAUGAGGAAAACGUUAUGUAAGAGGAGGAACCAAAUGGAACUGAUUGGAGGGAAAGAAGACGGUUGAGUAGUUCUUUAAAAAGUUCCGGGUUGGAUGCUUUCUAGUGGUUUUUCAACAGAGAGGCUAAGAAGGAAGAUAACUGAAAAUGGGACAUGCAUUGAUACUUUAGUAAUUUGAGGGUACAUUUUGAGUGUUAAGAAGUGAAGAGGAGGAGUCAUUUUCAGGGGCAAAAGAGUGUAUUGGUAGGAAGAUUAUAUAGGCAAUAUAAUUUACUUUAGAGCAGGGCUUUCCAACAGAACUUUUGGUAAUGAUGUCUAGUACAUUAGCCACAUGUGGCAGUCAAGCACUCAAAACAUGGCUAGUGUGGCUGAGGGGCUAAAAUUUAAUUGUAUUUCAUUGUAGUUCAUUUAAAUUUGGCUACCUGUGGCUAGUGGCUAUUAUAUUGGACAAUGCAUUUCUAAAUAUUCAGAUCCUGGGCAGAAGUUGGCUUUGACAUGAAGAAAGACUUCUUAGAAAGGAAGGAAGUAGACCGGGCAUGGUGGCUCAUGCCUGUAAUCCCAACACUUUGGGAAGCCGAGGCAGGUGGAUCACAAGGUCAAGAGAUCAAGACCAUCCUGGCCAACGUGGUGAAAACCUGUCUCUACUAAAAAUACAAAAAUUAGCUGGACAUGGUGGCACAUGCCUGUAGUCCCAACUACUCGAGAGGCUGAGGCAGGAGAGAAAAAAAAGAAGGAAAUAAGAGGGAGAUUGGGAGAAAAGUAAGGUGUUAUAGCUCUGAUCUGUGGUAUCUCCUGUUUUCCUUGCGGUAUGACUAGUGUGAGCCAAGGAUAGAGACCAACAAACUGGGGUACCAAAGUGGACAAUGAAGUACUAUGUAAUUAGUGCUAAUGCUAAAUUCAUUCCUUUGUUUAAGGCUUAAUAUCCUUGCAGAAGCCAUCCUGUGUUACUUGAGCCUGGACUAGUAUUGGGGUGAAGUCAAGCAUCAGAGUAAAACAUUUGUCCCCUUAAUGUUACCCCCUCUUAAUUUCUAAGAACCACAGGCCCAUUUUGCCCUUCCUUGUUACCAUCAUUGAGAUAAGGAAUAAGAUGUAGUAACCCCAAGUUAUCUGAUAGGUACAACUGACCUAUUCUGUUUGGCAGCUUUAUCUUAGACCUAUUCUGUUUGGCAGCUUUAUCUUAGCCCCAACCAAAUCUCUUCCUUUCACAUGGUGUUGGUUGAAUACUAUCCAACUCCAUGGGGUUGGUUUGUGUUUUUUUUUUUUUUUUUUUUUGAGACGGAGUCUUGCUCUGUUGCCCAGGCUGGAGUGCGGUGGUGUGAUCUUGGCUCACUGCAAGCUCCGCCUCCUGGGUUUAAGUGAUCCUCCUGCCUCAGCCUCCUGAAUAGCUGGGAUUACAGGCACGUGCAACCAAGCCCGGCUAAUUUUUGUGUUUUUAGUAGAGACUAGGUUUCAACAUGUUAGGCUGAUCUCAAACUCCUGACCUCGUGAUCUGCCCGCCUCGGCCUUCCAAAGUGCUGGGGUUACAGACUUGAGCCACUGCACCUGGCCAUGGGGUUGUUUCUUAAUUAGAUAUAGCUGAAAAGAACGCUAGACCAAAUAGGUUCUCUGCCUUGCCUUUUCGUUUGUUUUGUUUUAGCUAUUAUCAGGGAACCAAAAACUUUAAGGAGCUAGUACUGGUCUUAAUUUUUAAUAACUAGAGAUAGCAGAGUUAGAAACUAAGUUCAAAGUGAGAGAACAGCUGCAUUUGUCUUUCUGACCUCAUGCAAUUCCUAGGAAACUCUGUGUUCUGUGAUUUAGUCAGGCAAUAAAAUGCUCUCACUCCUU